GACAAGAAACCCUAGGAGACACCGCGGAGAACUCUGCCUCUGAGCUGGUGGGCGGGCCGGAUGUAGCCGAGCGCGGACAGGGCUAGUCCGGACAGAGUCCCAGAGCCAUGGGAGCGAAAAGAGACUGCUGCGGAUUAAGGAGGCCUUUCGGUUGGCGCAGCAGCCACACCACAACCAGGCGAAGCAGGUAGUGGCGCUGAAUCGCUCCUGCCGCGGGGUAAGCGCUCCCGGCCCGCGCCCGCCCCAGCCCCGACCUGGCGGGGCCAGGACGCUGGUUCAUACACUCCAAGAGAUAGAGUUUUGCUCUUGUUGCCCAGGCUGGAGUGCAAUGGCGCAAUCUUGGCUCACCGCAACCUCCACCUCCCGAGUUCAAGCGAUUCUCCUCCCACAACCUCCCGAGUAGCUGGGAUUACAGGCACCCGCCACCACGCCUGGCUAAUUUUGUAUUUUUAUUAGAGACGGGGUUUCUCCACGUUGGUCAGGCUAGUCUCGAACUCCUGACCUCAGGUGAUCCGCCCACAUUGGCAUCCCAAAGUGCUGGGAUUACAGGCGUGAUAAAUUGACCAUCUUAUACCAGGAAGUCAAAUGAGAAGACAUCAGUAAAAAUAUUCUGGCCAACUCAUGUUUUAUUUAUCAUAUCUUCAUCAUUAAUUGCUUCUCAUAAUGCCACAGUUUGUCAUGGUAUUUGUGGCAGCAGGCAAAGUCCUUGUUCAGACUUUGAUUAAAUUGCUGUGGCAUUUUUCUAUUAAAAAGAUCUCCUGUUUCAAUCUAUAGUUUGCCUGUGAUCUGUGGGUUAAAAAGAGCUAUUUUUUAAUACUAUUUUUAAUAGUAUUCAAAUGGAAUACUAUUCCAUUUGAUUCAGUGUUUUGAGAUAAUAUAUGAUUUUGCUUAGUCUCAUUUGGAUGAAAUGAAUAUUUCCAGAUCUACAUGUCAAAUAAGAGGGUACUGCAACUUGAAACUUGUGAUACUUUCUCACUACAUGGUGCAAACAGCUGAGUCAAGUUGUCCCUGAGAGUAGCCACCUUUCCCUCAGGCCAUACACAUGGAACCAUUCUUUCUCCCUACAAGUCAGCCCAUAAUAGAGCCUCUGGUUGAAAAUCAAGAUUUUGGUGUUCACUUGGCAAUAUUUACUAAGAGGUAAAUGACGCAAGCAGUACUCCAGCCAACCAAUCUAAGACUGACCGGCGUGAGCAGAGAACAGAGUCUCCAGGAGGUCUGUGGCCAGGGCCAGGCGAUUUAUGGGAAAGAGGCAGACAUUUUCCUGGCUUUCUAAAACCAAUUUUUCCAACAACAACGAUUUCCGUGCUCUUCUGCAGUCUUUGUAUGCUACUUUCAAGGAGUUCAAAAUGCAUGAGCAGAUUGAAAAUGAAUACAUUAUUGGUUUGCUUCAACAACGCAGCCAGACCAUUUAUAAUGUACAUUCUGACAAUAAACUCUCCGAGAUGCUUAGCCUCUUUGAAAAGGGACUGAAGAAUGUUAAGAAUGAAUAUGAACAGUUAAAUUAUGCAAAACAACUGAAAGAGAGAUUGGAGGCUUUUACAAGAGAUUUUCUUCCUCACAUGAAAGAGGAAGAGGAGGUUUUUCAGCCCAUGUUAAUGGAAUAUUUUACCUAUGAAGAGCUUAAGGAUAUUAAAAAGAAAGUGAUUGCACAACACUGCUCUCAGAAGGAUACUGCAGAACUCCUUAGAGGUCUUAGCCUAUGGAAUCAUGCUGAAGAGCGACAGAAGUUUUUUAAAUAUUCCGUGGAUGAAAAGUCAGAUAAAGAAGCAGAAGUGUCAGAACACUCCACAGGUAUAACCCAUCUUCCUCCUGAGGUAAUGCUGUCAAUUUUCAGCUAUCUUAAUCCUCAAGAGUUAUGUCGAUGCAGUCAAGUAAGCAUGAAAUGGUCUCAGCUGACAAAAACGGGAUCGCUUUGGAAACAUCUUUACCCUGUUCAUUGGGCCAGAGGUGACUGGUAUAGUGGUCCCGCAACUGAACUUGAUACUGAACCUGAUGAUGAAUGGGUGAAAAAUAGGAAAGAUGAAAGUCGUGCUUUUCAUGAGUGGGAUGAAGAUGCUGACAUUGAUGAAUCUGAAGAGUCUGCGGAGGAAUCAAUUGCUAUCAGCAUUGCACAAAUGGAAAAACGUUUACUCCAUGGCUUAAUUCAUAACGUUCUACCAUAUGUUGGUACUUCUGUAAAAACCUUAGUAUUAGCAUACAGCUCUGCAGUUUCCAGCAAAAUGGUUAGGCAGAUUUUAGAGCUUUGUCCUAACCUGGAGCAUCUGGAUCUUACCCAGACUGACAUUUCAGAUUCUGCAUUUGACAGUUGGUCUUGGCUUGGUUGCUGCCAGAGUCUUCGGCAUCUUGAUCUGUCUGGUUGUGAGAAAAUCACAGAUGUGGCCCUAGAGAAGAUUUCCAGAGCUCUUGGAAUUCUGACAUCUCAUCAAAGUGGCUUUUUGAAAACAUCUACAAGCAAAAUUACUUCAACUGCGUGGAAAAAUAAAGACAUUACCAUGCAGUCCACCAAGCAGUAUGCCUGUUUGCACGAUUUAACUAACAAGGGCAUUGGAGAAGAAAUAGAUAAUGAACACCCCUGGACUAAGCCUGUUUCUUCUGAGAAUUUCACUUCUCCUUAUGUGUGGAUGUUAGAUGCUGAAGAUUUGGCUGAUAUUGAAGAUACUGUGGAAUGGAGACAUAGAAAUGUUGAAAGUCUUUGUGUAAUGGAAACAGCAUCCAACUUUAGUUGUUCCACCUCUGGUUGUUUUAGUAAGGACAUUGUUGGACUAAGGACUAGUGUCUGUUGGCAGCAGCAUUGUGCUUCUCCAGCCUUUGCGUAUUGUGGUCACUCAUUUUGUUGUACAGGAACAGCUUUAAGAACUAUGUCAUCACUCCCAGAAUCUUCUGCAAUGUGUAGAAAAGCAGCAAGGACUAGAUUGCCUAGGGGAAAAGACUUAAUUUACUUUGGGAGUGAAAAAUCUGAUCAAGAGACUGGACGUGUACUUCUGUUUCUCAGUUUAUCUGGAUGUUAUCAGAUCACAGACCAUGGUCUCAGGGUUUUGACUCUGGGAGGAGGGCUGCCUUAUUUGGAGCACCUUAAUCUCUCUGGUUGUCUUACUAUAACUGGUGCAGGCCUGCAGGAUUUGGUUUCAGCAUGUCCUUCUCUGAAUGAUGAAUACUUUUACUACUGUGACAACAUUAACGGUCCUCAUGCUGAUACCGCCAGUGGAUGCCAGAAUUUGCAGUGUGGUUUUCGAGCCUGCUGCCGCUCUGGCGAAUGACCCUUGACUUCUGAUCUUUGUCUACUUCAUUUAGCUGAGCAGGCUUUCUUUCAUGCACUUUACUCAUAGCACAUUUCUUGUGUUAACCAUCCCUUUUUGAGCGUGACUUGUUUUGGCCCCAUUUCUUACAACUUCAGAAAUCUUAAUUUACCAGUGAAUUGUAAUGUUGUUUCUCUUGCAAAUUAUACUUUUGGUUUAGAAAGGGAUUAGGUCUUUUCAAAAGGGUGAGAACAGUCUUACAUUUUUCUUUUAAAUGAAAUGCUUUAAAGAAUGUUGGUAAUGCCAUGUCAUUUAAAGUAUUUCAUAGAUAAUUUUGAGUUUUAAAGUCCAUGGAGGUGAUUGGUUCUCUUUACACAUUAACACUGUACCAAGCUUUGCAGAUCUUUUCCGACACACAUGUCUGAAGACUUAUUUUCAAAGACAGCACAUUUUUGGAAACUAAUCUCUUUUCCGUAAUAUUUCCUUUAUUUCAAUGAUUCUCAGAAGGCCAAUUCAAACAAACCCACAUUUAAGGUUCUUUAGGAUUAUAGAAUAAAUUGGCUUCUGAGUGUUAGCUCAGUGAGCUAGGAAAGCACCAAUCGAUAUUUGUUUCCUUUAGGGAUACUUUGUUCUCACCACUGUCCCUAUGUCAUCAAAUUUGGGAGAGAUUUUUUAAAAUACCACAAUCAUUUGAAGAAAUGUAUAAAUAAAAUCUACUUUGAGGACUUUACCAAGUAAUACUGUUGUGUUGUGAUUUUUAUUAUAAAUCUCAAUCCAGGUUUACUUUAGUAUAGAAUAGGACUACAUACUUUGUCUUUGGACCUCCCAUGAACUUAUUACCCUGACAAAUAGUUUUAGACAGAUACUGAAUUUUAUUGAGCUGAAUUUUCUUUUUGAAAUGAGUUAUUCAGUAGUCAAAAUUUGAAUCCGUAAGUAUAUCUACUUUGCUUUGUUAAAACAUCAUGAGAGUGGAGGCCUGCCACCCAGAAAGGCACAUACUAGUGCCUUUUAGUACAAUUUUAUGUCAUGUAGAAGAAAAUGGCAAUGUUCCUCCUAUUGAUACAGAUACAGGCAUAUGUCAUCUUAUUGCGUUUUGCUUUAUUGCACUUUGCAAAUAAUGCAUUUUUUACAAAUGGAAGGUUUAUGGCAACUCUGCGUUGAGCCAGUCUAUUGGUGCCAUGUUUCCAAUAAAACUUCUCCUUUCAUGUCUCGUAUAUUGUGAUAAUUCUUGGAGUAUUUCAUAGUUUUUCACUAUUAUUAAAUCUGUUGUGGUGAUCUGUGGCCAGUGAUUGUUGUUACUAUUGUAAUUGCUUUGGAAUGCCAUGAACUGUGCCCUAAUAAGACAGAGAACUUAAUUGAUAAA